UUUUUUUUCCUUUUUCUCUUUUUAGGACUGACUGACUAUGUUCACUGAUUCAUAGAAACUUUAAGAGAUAAUAAGUGUGUUUUGUUUUCAGCCAUAAGGUUUUAGGGUGAUUUGUUAUGCAGCAGUAGAUACCUAAGAUACUCUCCAUAAUAGGACUUCAUAAGUCAGUCUAAUUCUUAAGAAAGGAAUAACAAAUCCAAGAAGUGGGACCCCUGUAAUAAAGCAAUAUAUCUAGAUAUCCAGGAUCAUUUUUUAUCUUUUAGUGGUGGGAGACCAAUUCCCCUUUAUAGCAUGGAAAUGCUUGGUGGUGAGGAGCCUGGUAUCUGGAACUGUGUUCAGGAGAAGUUAUCAGCGUGAUUAAAGUAAAACAAAGUCUGGGCCGGGCGCGGUGGCUCACGCCUGUAAUCCCCAGCACUUUGGGAGGCCGAGGUGCACGGAUCACAAGGUCAGGAGAUCGACACCAUCCUGGCUAACACGGUGAAAACCCGUCUCUACUAAAAAUACAAAAAAUUAGCUGGGCGUGGUGGCGGGGUGCCUGUAGUCCCAGCUACUCGGGAGGCUGAGGAAGGAGAAUGGCGUGAACCCAGAAGGCAGAGCUUGCAGUGAGCCGAGAUUGCGCCAUUGCACUCCAGCCUGGGCGACAGAGCGAGACUCCGUCUCAAAAAAACAAACAAACAAAAAACAAGCAAAAAAAAAAAAAACAAAGUCUGUCCAUCUUAGCAACCACUUUGAUACUGGAGAAAGGCUCCUGUCCAGAAGGAAGGGCACAGUAGUGAGGUACUUGCCAAUGAGCUGGGUAGAGCUGCCACUGGCUGGCUUCGGGAAGUGUUUAUCACUGACUGGCUCAUGUUCAGAAGCUUGGAGUGAGGCUGUUGUGUACUGGUUGAUUUUCAGAGUACGUGUACUGAUCUAAAAUUAUGUAAAUUAAUGGCAAGUACUUGUUAGUGACUUGGGACUUUGGUCAAAAAACAGUCUUUUCCUUUCCUGAAUAUGAAAAGUAAGUUCUUUUAAUUAGCAGCCUCCCCUCUUCACUGUUUUUUCUUCCUGCAGUCCAACUAACAGAACAGACCAUAAAGGUCUGUCCAGAUCAUUAUUUAUGGAAGUAUGAGAUAUAUAUAUUUCAGCUGGUGUUAACAUUUUAUUUAAGUGCCAGUUACUGAGCAGAAAAAUAGCUGUAACUACGAGUUUUUGUAAUUUAUUGGAAAAAGCUAAAUAUAAGACAUUUAGGGUGUCCUCCCAAAGUCAACACAGGACAAGAUCAUUUAAUAUAGGACAUGUCCUGUGUAUACAGGAUGCCUAGCAACUGUAUGUAGCCACGGGUGUUUUGGUUGUUAAAUGAAUCUGUCCUAAAAGGUUCUACGCACAUCUAGGUCCUUGGAAGGGAGAGGGCUAAAACGGCGAGUGGAAACCAUGGUUUCCCUGAGGACUGCCCAGCUGAGGACCCAAGCAAGAUCCUGGGCUUGGGCCUCUUAGAGAUGACAAAGCAGGCGCCAUUCUCCCCUCACCUGCACGGCCCAGGCUUCAGCUCUUGAGGAUCUUGCUUGUCCAAACCCAGAAGACAGUGCAUGAAGCCAGGGGACAUCCGCCAUGCUCCAAACAACUUGGCCUCAGAUGUUUUGGGGAUUCUAGUAGCCCUUGGGUUUGAUGACUUCAGAGGAGAGUUUUGCAAUCAGCAGCCUCCAGAAAUACUGGUAGCGUUUCCAUUCCCCAAACCUGCUCUGAUCUCCCACCUGGAGAGAGGGGAAGCACCAUGGGGCCCAGAUCCCUGGGACACCGAGAUUCUGAGAGGCAUCAGUCAAGGUGGUGAGUCCUGGAUCAAAAAUGAAGGGCUAGUUAUAAAGCAGGAAGCCUCUGAAGAAACAGAGUUGCACAGAAUGCCAGUAGGAGGACUUCUCAGGAACGUUUCUCAGCACUUUGAUUUUAAAAGGAAGGCACUGAAGCAGACUUUCAAUCUAAAUCCAAAUCUGAUACUUCGAGGUGGAAUGAAGUUCUAUGAAUGUAAAGAAUGUGGGAAAAUCUUCCGAUAUAACUCAAAGCUUAUUCGGCAUCAGAUGAGUCAUACUGGGGAAAAGCCCUUUAAGUGUAAGGAGUGUGGCAAAGCUUUCAAGUCCAGCUAUGAUUGUAUUGUACAUGAGAAAAACCACAUUGGAGAAGGGCCCUAUGAAUGUAAGGAGUGUGGCAAAGGUUUGAGUUCCAACACAGCCUUGACUCAACAUCAGAGGAUCCACACUGGAGAGAAACCCUAUGAAUGUAAAGAGUGUGGAAAGGCUUUCCGUAGGAGUGCGGCAUACCUGCAGCAUCAGAGAUUACACACGGGAGAGAAACUCUAUAAAUGUAAGGAAUGUUGGAAAGCUUUCGGUUGUAGGUCACUUUUUAUUGUCCAUCAGAGAAUUCAUACUGGGGAGAAACCUUAUCAAUGUAAGGAGUGUGGCAAAGCCUUCACCCAGAAAAUAGCCUCCAUUCAGCAUCAGAGAGUUCACACUGGGGAGAAGCCUUAUGAAUGUAAGGUGUGUGGGAAAGCCUUCAAAUGGUAUGGAAGUUUUGUUCAGCAUCAGAAAUUGCACCCUGUGGAGAAGAAGCCAGUCAAGGUCCUUGGGCCAUCCCUGGUCAGUCCCCAGUGCUCCUCUCCAGCCAUACCUCCUGUUCUUCUCCAGGGAUCCUGUUCUGCUUCAGCCGUAGCUGUGCCUUCACUGACCUUUCCACAUGCUGUGCUCAUUCCUACCUCUGGGAAUUUUUUCAUGCUGCUGCCUACAUCUGGAAUACCUUCUUCAUCUGCCCAAAUAGUGCGUGUCUUCCAGGGUCUUACUCCCACUGUGAAACCUUCCCCAGUUAUUCUCACCCCUUCUUCUCACUCCUCAUGAGCUUUAUCUUGGCAGUCUUACGGCUCUUAUGCCUAGCAAAUCUCCAGCCUAAUUUUAUAUAUUUUUUUGAGAAAGGGUCUUGCUCUGUCACCCAGGCUAGAGUGCGGUGGUGUGAUCUUGGCUCACUGCAACCUCCCCCUCCUGGGUUCAAGCGAUUCUCCUCCUUCAGACUCUCGAAUAGCUGGGAUUACAGGCACGCCUCACCACGCCCAGCUAAUUUCUGUAUUUUUAGAAGAGAUGGGGUUUCGCCAUCUUGGCCAGGCUGGUCUCAAACACCUGACCUCAAGUGAUCCGCCUGCCUUGGCCCCCCAAAGUGCUGGGAUUACAGGAGUGAGCCACUGUGCCCAGCCUCCAACCUAAUUUGAGUUUCAUUUGUAUUUUUUUCAUCACCUUACAUGUGUUAACAGCUGUUUCAACAUAAACUCCAUUAUAAUCUAUAUACAUUUAAAGACCGUGUUUACAUAAUCUCUUCUGGGUAGAAAAUGGAAAUACUUAACCUUUGCAUUGGUCCCUUUCAGGCUUGAACAACAGUGGCUGUAUCUGCAUCGUGGGGUUGCUGGUGGUAGAACACUUUGGUGUUAGGAAAGUUUGGAAAAGAGGAUAUCCCUGUAUUAGGCCAUUAUGAUUAGAGAUAAGCAGCCUGGGAGAAACAUACAAGACCUGUGGCUACUGGUAGAGAAUUGGAAUAAGCUUCCAACAAUGGACUGUAGAGAUUAAUGGAGAUUGUUUAGUGGGCCCAUGGCUAGGUGGGGUAUUAAUACAGUUGAAGUUAUGUUGCCCUUGGCACAGAUCUUUGAGAAUCUCAUACAUCUGUGAAAAAGAUAAUGUGAAAUAAACAGUAAAAAAAAAAAGUAUGUUGAUGGCAGUGAGAGUAAUCAUGUCUUUAAACGUGAAGUUUUUUUUUCUUUAGUUUUGCUCUUGAUAGCUAGAUGUUUCUUUUAACUUUUAUUUCGUAAGUAAAUAUACACAAAGGCAUUCAUCUUUGUUGAAUCUGUUGUGCAGAUUUUUCUUGAUGAGCAUUCUGUUUUUUUUUCUUUGUGAGCACUGGCUUCUAUAUUUUAUUUCAUAUUUAUGAAUUAUAAAUAUGAAUUUAAUUACUAAAGAAAUAAAAAUAAUGGUGUAAAGCCAACUCGAGGGGAAUCUGAAUAAGCUUCCAAAAUUUUUUUUUUUAAGAAAUAAAGGGAGCUGUGUAGUGGGUCAGUGGCUAGGUAGGUUAGUGAAGUGGAAUUUGGGGUUGCUCUUGGAAGUGGCCUUGAUGAGGAUCCUUUACAACUAUUCAGAGGACUGUGUGAAGUAGUUACUGGAAAAAGAACUUGAAUUAUGCAUUUAUUGGCAUUAAUGUAAACAGUAAGUCCUAAGCUUUGAUGGAAGGGUCCAUACAUUUUUUUUUUUUUUUUGCUGAUGUUGCUAUCUAGAUGUUUCUCUAUAGCAAUUAAUAGCAAAACCUUUACAUUCUUGGUUUUUAAACUUUACCAUGUGUCUGAAUUACAUAGUGUGCUUGUAAAAAGAAGAGUUUUCUCUCUUGCACAAAUUCUGAUUUUGGCUAUCUGUGGUGAUGGCCAGAUCUUUAGCAUGGACCAUACUUUGAGAGAUAUGCUUCAAACAGAAAAUGCCCACCCCUCCUCCUUUACCCAGCAUAAACUCUAUGGUUAAUUCUUAAAAUAAUGCCUUACAGUCUCCAUUAACUCCCUUGCCCUUCUCUUGCUUUGUCAUGCUCGCUUGGCAAAACCUCAUCUCUGACUAAAUGCAGUUCUUUGCCUUCUCUGUUCCUGCACCAAAAAUGAUCAGGAGAAAGCAUAUUACCAGGCUGAACUGUCACUUUAAAUUCAUGACCAGUAACUUCAUGGAGGCCCUUAACGUUUCCUGAUGGUCAUACUACAAUUUUUGGAGUCCACUUAACUCCCCUGCUUUCCUAGGCCACUACUUUAUACUUUCUCUCUUCUGUAACUUCCAAAGCAUCCCUCUCAGUUCUCAUGCUCAGCUGAUGGUUAUGUUUCUGCCUUCGGCGAGAGAACAGCAAGCUCCAGAAAGUGGCUGCGCCUUCAGCCCCGUGCUAGAAUGAGAACAUAUGGAGCCAACUUGAGUUCGGAAGGGCUGUGGCCACCUCGUUUCGCCCAUCUACUUUUCACCUUGCCGUAUCUGAUUCUUCACCACCGUAUUCUCAGUCACUUCCACUAAACAGUGCCAGUGUUUUAAGGUUCUGUCACACUCAGUAACCCACUUCUGGUUCCUCAUUCCGUGUCAGUGAUCAGCAGUAGACUGAAGAAUCUACCUUAGAUUUGCUCCAUACUAUUAAUUAGCUUACAAAAUGUCUAAGAGGAGCUAAGCUGGGAUGCCACAUAGGCAGAAGCCAGGAAAAAUGACCAACCACAGAACCAAGUGGUUCCAGUGGAAACUCAGCAGCUGCUGGUGCCUGCUACUGGACUGCCACCCCCCAUUGAAGAGACUGGACCACCAGGAAGGUCGUUUCACAUUCUGUAGUAAAAAUACCCCUACAAUCAUUUUGGUAGGGUCUUCUGUCUUCAGCCAGGGUGUACCUGCUCGGUGGGAGUUGGUUAUAUAUGUAUGUCCAAGUUGCAGGGGCUUCUGGGAAAUACAGGUUUUGGAUUCUGCCUGGGAAGAGAGUCAUAGUAUGAAGAAGUCUGAAAAUGGGGAAGGGAUUUUCAGAAUAUGUUGAGCAGCUGUAAAAUAUCAGAUACCCAUUAUAGGCAUUGAAGGUUACCUAAAUGACAGAAGGAUGCACUAUAUUCAUGGGUAGGAAAGAUUAGUUUCAUCAAGAUUUCAAUUUUUAUCAAUUCAUAAAUUAAAAACAAUAUAAAAAUUCCAGAGGGGUGUGUGUAUAGAGAGGCAAAGGACACAGAGUAGCUAACCUAGUUUUGAAGAACAAGAUGGGGGGUUUUAUGCUACCAGAUAUUAUAUACAAUGAUCAUCAAACACAGAACAAAGCAAAAAACAAACUCCCCAAACCCAAGUUGAAACAAAAAAAACCCCCAGACUGUAAUAGUAUUAUUAUUAUUUUUUAAGAUGGAAUCUUGCUCUGUUGCUCAGGCUGGAGUGCAGUGGUGCAAUCUUGGCUCACUGCAACCUACACCUCCCGGGUUCAAGUGAUUCUCUUGCCUCAGCCUCCUGAGUAGUGUGUGCCACCACGCCCAGCUAAUUUUUUAAUUUUUAGUAGAGACAGGGUUUCACCAUGUUGGCCAGGCUGGUCUUGAACUCCUGGCAGCCUCAAGUGAUCCACCCACCUCGGUCUCCCAAAGUGUUGGGAUUACAGGCGUGAGCCACUGCACCUGGCCUGUAACAUGAUUUGCUGAAAUUUUUAAAAAUCUUAAAUAAUGUACUGUUUAGAAAUAUACAUAUUUUAUACAAAAUUAUAAAGAAAGCAUAGAGAGGUAAGCAUUAGUGGCACAGCUGAGAAAAUAUAAAAGGUAGUUCUGUCUCUAUCCUGUCUCCUUUAUUCUGCUACUGCUCUCAUUCUGUCUCAUCCCAGGAAUCCAGUCCCAAGUGCUGCCUGCCAAUCGUCCAGCACCCUCCACCUUUGCCACCUAUUUCUUGUUGUAAAACAGAUGUUUGUUUCUAAAAUAUAAUGAAUUAAUGAUUAUCAAAGUACAGGCAUACCUCAUUUUAUUGCAGUUUGUUUUAUUGUGUCUUGCGGAUAUUGCAUUUUUUACAAACUGAAGGUUUGUGGCAGGCCUGUGUUGAGCAAGACUAUCAGUGCCAUUUUUUUUCAACAGCAUGUGCUCAUUUCAUUUUUCUGUGUCUUACACAGAAACUUAAAAUAUUUCAAACUUUUCAUUAUAUGUGUUUUGGUGAUUAGUGACUUUUAUGUUUCUAUUGUAAUUGUUUUGGGGUGCCACAGACUGCAUCCAUCUAAGACAGUGAGCUUAGUUGAUGUGUGUGUGUGUGUUCUGAUUACUCCACUAACUGAUGGUUCCCCAUCUCUCUCCCUCUCCUCAGACCUCACUAUUCUCUCAGACACAACAGUAUUGAAAUUAGACCAAUUGAUAACCUUACAAACACCUUUAAGUGUUUAAGUGAAAAAGUCACAUGCCUCUCACUUUAAAUCAAAAGCUAGAAAUGAUUAAGCUUAGUGAGGAAGGCUAAUGUCAACAGCUGAGAUAGGCCAAAAGCUAGACUGCUUCUGCCAAACAGUCAAGUUGUGAAUGCAAAAGAAAAGUUCUUGAAGGAAAUGAAAAGUACUUCUCCAGGGAACACAUGAACGAUAAUAAAGUGGCCAGGUGCAGUGGCUGACACCUAGAAUCCCAGCACUUCGGGGAGCCAAAGCGGGAGGAUCCCCUGAAGCCAGGAGUCCGAGACCAGCUUGGGCCACAAAGUGAGACCCCUGUCUCUACAAAAAAUUAAAAAUUUAGCUGGGUGUGGUUGUGCAUGCCUGUAGUCCGAUCUACUUGGGAGGCUGAAGUGAGAGGAUCCCUUUAGCCAGGGAGUUCGAGACUGCAGUGAGCUAUGAUUGUGCCACUGCACUCUAGCCUGUGUGACAGAAUGAAACCAAAAAAAGUGAAACAGCAUUAUUACUGAUAUGGAGAAAGUUUUAGGGGUCUGGAUCAAACCAACCACAAAUUCCCUUAAGCCAAAACCUAAUCCAGAGCAAGGCCAUAACUGCCAUUGUAUGAAGGCUGAGAGAAGUGAGGAAGCUGCAGGAAAGUUUGAAGCUAGCAGAGGUUGGUUCAUGAGGUUUAAGAAGUCAUCUUAUCAUAAAAGUGCAAGGUGAAGCAGCAAGUGCUGGUGUAGAAGCUGUAGCAAUUUAUCCAGAUCUAGCUAAGUUAAUUGAUGAAGUUGCUACACCACGAGAUUUUCAGUGUAUUCCAAACAGCCUUCUUUUGGAAGAAGAAACCAUCUAGGACUUUCAUGGAGAAGAGAAGUUAAUCCCUGGCUUAAAAGCAUCAAAGGACAGCUCGUCUCUCUUGUUAGGGGUUCAUGCAGCUGGUAACUUUAAGUUGAAGCCAAUGCUCAUUUACCAUUCAGAAAAUCCUAGGGCCCAUAAGAAUUAUGCUAAAUCCACUCUGCCUGUGCUCUAGAAAUGGAAGAUCAAAGCCUGGAUGACAGCACAUCUGUUUACAGCAUGGAUUACUGAAUAUUUUAAGCCCACUGUUGAGACCUACUAAAUAUUAGGAAAAAAGAAUUCUGUCAGGUGUGGUGGCUCACACUUGUAAUCCCAACACUUUGGGAGGCCAAGGCAGGUGGAUCAGUUGAGGUCAGGAGUUUGAGACCAGCCUGACCAACAUGGAGAAACCCUAUCUCUACUAAAAAUACAAAAAUUAGCUGGAUGUGGUGGUGUGUGCCUGUAAUCCCAGCUACUUGGGAGGCUGAGGCAGGAGAAUUGCUUGAAUCCAGAGGCAGAGGUUGCAGUGAGCUGAGGUUGCACCACUGUGCUUCAGCCUGGGUAACAGAGUGAGACUGUCUCAAAAAAAAAAAAAAUUUAGUUCCAAAUAUUACUGCUCGUUGAUAAUGUGUCUGGUCACCCAAGAGUUCUGAUGGAGAUGUACAAAGAGAUUAAUGUUUUUAUGUCUGCUAAACAACAUCCAUUCUGCAGGAUCCAUUACUCCAUGGGUCAAGGAGUAAUUUUGACUUUCAAGUAUUAUUUAAGGAAUACAUUUUGUAAGGCUGUGGCUGCCAUAGUGGUUGUUCUGUACAAAGUAACUUGAAAACCUUCUGGAAAGGAUUCAUCAUUCUAGAUGCCAUUAAGGACAUUUGUGAUUCAUGGGAGAAGGUCAAAAUAUCAACAUUAACAGGAGUUCAGAAGACAUUGACCUCAACCCUGAUGGAUGAUCUUGAGGGGUUCAAGACUUCAGUGGACGAAGUAACUGCAGAUGUGGUGGAAAUAGCAAGAUAACUAGACUUAGAAGUGGAACCUGCAUAUGUGACUGAAUUGCUGCAAUCUCAUGAUAAAACGUGAACAAAUGAGGAGUUGCUUCUAAUAUAAGAGCCACAAAAGUGGUUUCUUGAGAUGGAAACUACUCCUGGUGAAGAUCCUGUGACCAUUGUUGAAAUGACAACAAAGGACUUAGAAUAUUACAUAAACUUAGUUGAUAAAACAGCAGCAGAGUUUGAGAGGAUUGACUUCAAUUUUGAAGAAUGUUCCACUGUGGGUAAAAGGCUAUCCAACAGCAACACAUGCUACAGAUAAAUCUUUCGGAAAGGAAGAGUCAGUUGAUGUUGCAGCCUUCCUUGUUGUCUCAUUUAAAGAAAUCUCUAGAGCCACACUAACCUUCAGCAACCACCACACCGAUCAUUCAGCAGCCAUCAACAGUGAGGCAAGACUGUCUUCCAGCAACAAAGACUCACUGAAGACUUAGAUUAUCGUUAACAUCUUUUAGCAAUAAAAUAUUUUUAAAUUAAAGUAUGUACAUUGUCAGAUAUAAUGCUAUUGCAAACUUAAUAGACUAUAAUAUAGAUUAAACAUAACUUUUAUAGGUACUGGAAAAUAAAAAUAAUUGUGUGACUCCCUUUAUUGUGUUAAACAUUUUAUUACAGUUGUCUGGAAGCAAACCUGCAAUAUCUCCAAGAUAUGCCUGUAUUUUUCAAAAUGUGGUCUUUUAACAUUGCUAUGAAGUUUAUCAGUAAUAAUAUCUUAUUUCAUGGUUGUCCAGAAGUUACAUAACUUGUCUUAAUCUAAAAAUCAUAUCAUUUAAAAAGCCUGAUGAUUUAAUAUUUUUCAUAAAGAAAACUUUUGACAA